CCCAGUCUUCUUCCACCGGAAGAAGGCACAACCUGCAUCUGCAGCCCCAGGGCCAUUGGGUUAGGCCUGUGGCCAAACUACUAAGGUGCUGGGAGACUGAGGAGGCCCAGCUCCUCCUGGGGCCACCAAGCCCGUGGUUGACGGCCUCCCCAUGGACCGGGCUGUCCCGAGAGCAGCAAGUCAGCCGGGGCCCUCAGGGCCGCUGAGGCCACUGCUCAGUGUCGCCGUAAUGGAAACUUCUCAGCUGGUUGUGAGCCGCAACAGCUCUGGUUCACACCCUGCGACAGCGAGGCUGUGACCGCCAGUGGAUCUCGGGGCUGAUCAGGCCUGAGCCACCCCGGAGGUACAGCACCAGCAGGAGCCCAGGACCAUGUUCCAGUAAAUGAGGACUGCAGCAGGAGCCGUGAGCCCUGACUCCCGGCCAGAGACACGACGUCAGACCAGAAAGAAUGAGGAGGCCGCGUGGGGCCCGCGGGUGUGCAGGGCAGAGAGGGAGGACAACAGGAAGUGCCCCCCCUCCAUCCUGAAACGGAGCCGGCCGGAGCACCACCGCCCAGAGGCCAAGCCCCAGAGGACCUCGAGGCGCGUGUGGUUCCGAGAACCCCCAGCGGUGACCGUCCACUACAUUGCUGACAAGAACGCCACAGCCACUGUCAGGGUGCCCGGCCGGCCCAGGCCACACGGCGGCUCCCUGCUCCUGCAGCUGUGUGUGUGCGUCCUGCUCGUGCUGGCCCUGGGCCUAUACUGCGGCCGGGCCAAGCCCGUGGCAACGGCACUGGAGGACCUGCGGGCCCGGCUCCUCGGCCUUGUCCUGCACCUGCGGCACGUGGCCCUCACCUGCUGGCGCGGCCUCCUGCGGCUCUGACGGGCAGGACGGGCAGGACGGGCAGGGCUUCCAGGAGAGCUCAAGCACUCCGGGGGCUCCGAGACAGCCUGAGCCCUGGCCCUGCUGCUUGGUGAAUCAUGGGGGCCAAAAGGGGCUGCUGCCUGAGGGCUAACUAGGAAAAGGGGGACCCCGUGGCGUGAGAUCGGACAUGGGGGGCACAGCAGGCGGCCCCGCCACACUAGUCAGCACAGCCCUCCUGUCUCCUGUGUUGGGUCCAUGUGAGAUUUUAUUAGAAAGAGGAUUCGACUGCUAACAGUUGAGGCUCCCCAGGCUCACCCAAAGACCCCUCCCUCGUCCCAGCAGGAACUCCUGCUGCUGCUAGGGCCUGGCCCGGCCAUCACCGUGUGCACCCUCUUGAGGAGGGGGACACACUGCCCGUGUUCAAGGGGCUGCUCGGAGGAGGCAAACCCAGCCUUUUGCGAUUAUGGCUUGUGGGGAAUCCAGACCUCGAAACCCCACGGGGAGGGAAGGGUCUGGUUGUCAAGGUGGGUCCCUUUGAUGUGAGGUGCCAUCCUCUGAGCCCAGGUCUGACCCCCCUACCCAGCCCCGUGAGUCUGGAGAGGCCCCAGGGAAGGACCCCUCAUCAGGGGCGGCUUCAGGUGUAGAAGCCGAGGGGACAGCAAGGGGCCCAGACACCCCCGACCUUCAGAACAGCCAUCUGUGCCCAGCUCUGCAGGCCAGGCACACCCAGCUGAGCCCGGGGCCAGCCAGCACCACCCACCAGCUGGGGCCUGUGGGUCCCGGAGACCGUCUGUGGUUGUGGCUUUGUCGCCGGAUUGCAGAGCUGAAGGGAGCCCUGUGGAUGACAAACACCAGGGGCCUCUCCAGACCCUACGUGGGGGGAGGGCUGAACAAAGCAGGGAGGCCCACGGUUAGACACCAGGCAGAACUGCCCAGGAGAGACACAGGGACAAUCAGACCAGCGUCCUCGAGGUUAGCCUGAGGCGGGUGGGCACGGCCGACCAUCCACCCGGUGGUUCCUGUUUGUCCCACCACUUAACUGGGAGACACUGUUUUAUUAAAACACACCGUGGCUUCCUUCAGUCUUGGUGUUUUUAUAGAAAUGAGAGAAACCAGAACCGAUUUGCUAAGGAAUCGGCCUCAGUGGCCAAAGCGGAUGUCCUGGGCGCCUGGAACCUCCCCAUCUCCUGCAGGCCUGGGAGUGGAUGUGUCCACUCGGGCAGGGGCUGACCAAGCCCCUGGGUCUUGAGGGAUGCCCGGCCGGCUCCCUUUGCCCUGCAGUCAGGGUGUGUCCCUGCAACUCCAGGUGCCAGGGAACAGGUGAAGUGGUCUCCAGGGUCACUUCCAGCUUUGGAAUCCAGGGAGCCCAGAGUUGCGGGUGGAGGUAACAAAAGGGGCUGUUUCCAGAAGUGGCCCAGAAGGGACCAUGGUGGGGGCUCCCCCGGGGACCCUCCAGCAUCUCUCCCCAGGCCCAGCCCAUCCCACCCCACCCCAGGAAGGAGGAUGGGCAGGUUCCUGCCCCAUAUUCUGGAUGCAGAAGCAGCGGCUCCCAGAGGUUGGGUCUCUCAGAGCAGUCACAGGCCCAGGCUCAGCCCUGUGUGCUUGGGACACCCCUCCAGCCCCGGUUCUGACGGGGGACACCGCACAGGCCGAUCUCCCCCAGCCGCUGCUGUCUGUCCACUGCAAAGGCAACGCAAGGACGUGCCUGGCUUUGCGGGGUCCCACGCUACGACCUCAGGUGUUUUCGAAU